GCAGCUUCUCUCGCCGCCGCGCCCCCAGCUGCUCUGGUUACGGUUGGUGUUUGCGAAUUCUCUGCGGCACCUUCUUCGCUGAACUCCACCGUCAGUUCCAUAGGCGCGCGCCCGCGUCACGUGGGCCGAGGUUCCGGCGCGGCUGCUGGCCGGCGGCUGAGCCGGGAGAAAGGAGCUGCGGCCACCGUUCGCCCUACUUCUGCGCCUCGGGGCGGGCGCGCCGGUAAAAAUGGCGAAAUGGGGGUAGGCGGCGCUGGACCUGAAGAGAUGGGGCGCGCAGGUGGGGCGGUUGUCAGAGCCCCCUGACGUGGGCGCCGGGCUUUUAUCGGCGAUUUGAUCUGGCGACCUCGGGCCGGCGCCUAAGAGGUCAGACUGCGGAGCCUGCGGGUCGCCAGCGGCCCCGCCGAGAGCCGGAGGCAAUGGAUGAACAGAGCGUGGAGAGCAUUGCUGAGGUUUUCCGAUGUUUCAUUUGUAUGGAGAAAUUGCGGGAUGCACGCCUGUGUCCUCAUUGCUCCAAACUGUGUUGUUUCAGCUGUAUUAGGCGCUGGCUGACAGAGCAGAGAGCUCAAUGUCCUCAUUGCCGUGCUCCACUCCAGCUACGAGAACUAGUAAAUUGUCGUUGGGCAGAAGAAGUAACACAACAGCUUGAUACUCUUCAACUCUGCAGUCUCACCAAACAUGAAGAAAAUGAAAAGGACAAAUGUGAAAAUCACCAUGAAAAACUUAGUGUAUUUUGCUGGACUUGUAAGAAGUGUAUCUGCCAUCAGUGUGCACUUUGGGGAGGAAUGCAUGGCGGACAUACCUUUAAACCUUUGGCAGAAAUUUAUGAGCAACACGUCACUAAAGUGAAUGAAGAGGUAGCCAAACUUCGUCGGCGUCUCAUGGAACUGAUCAGCUUAGUUCAAGAAGUGGAAAGGAAUGUAGAAGCUGUAAGAAAUGCAAAAGAUGAGCGUGUUCGGGAAAUUAGGAAUGCAGUGGAGAUGAUGAUUGCACGGUUAGACACACAGCUGAAGAAUAAGCUUAUAACACUGAUGGGUCAGAAGACAUCUCUAACCCAAGAAACAGAGCUUUUGGAAUCCUUACUUCAGGAGGUGGAGCACCAGUUGCGGUCUUGUAGUAAGAGUGAGUUGAUAUCUAAGAGCUCAGAGAUCCUUAUGAUGUUUCAGCAAGUUCAUCGGAAGCCCAUGGCAUCUUUUGUUACCACUCCUGUUCCACCAGACUUUACCAGUGAAUUAGUGCCAUCUUACGAUUCAGCUACUUUUGUUUUAGAGAAUUUCAGCACUUUGCGUCAGAGAGCAGAUCCUGUUUACAGUCCACCUCUUCAAGUUUCAGGACUUUGCUGGAGGUUAAAAGUUUACCCAGAUGGAAAUGGAGUUGUGCGAGGUUACUACUUAUCUGUGUUUCUGGAGCUCUCAGCUGGCUUGCCUGAAACUUCUAAAUAUGAAUAUCGUGUAGAGAUGGUUCACCAGUCCUGUAAUGAUCCUACAAAAAAUAUCAUUCGAGAAUUUGCAUCUGACUUUGAAGUUGGAGAAUGCUGGGGCUAUAAUAGAUUUUUCCGUUUGGACUUACUCGCAAAUGAAGGAUACUUGAAUCCACAAAAUGAUACAGUGAUUUUAAGGUUUCAGGUACGUUCACCAACUUUCUUUCAAAAAUCCCGGGACCAGCAUUGGUACAUUACUCAGUUGGAAGCUGCACAGACUAGUUAUAUCCAACAAAUAAACAACCUUAAAGAGAGACUUACUAUUGAGCUGUCUCGAACUCAGAAGUCAAGAGAUUUGUCACCACCAGAUAACCAUCUUAGCCCCCAAAAUGAUGAUGCUCUGGAGACACGAGCUAAGAAGUCUGCAUGCUCUGACAUGCUUCUCGAAGGUGGUCCUACUACAGCUUCUGUAAGAGAGGCCAAAGAGGAUGAAGAAGAUGAGGAGAAGAUUCAGAAUGAAGAUUAUCAUCACGAGCUUUCAGAUGGAGAUCUGGAUCUGGAUCUUGUUUAUGAGGAUGAAGUAAAUCAGCUCGAUGGCAGCAGUUCCUCUGCUAGUUCCACAGCAACAAGUAAUACAGAAGAAAAUGAUAUUGAUGAAGAAACUAUGUCUGGAGAAAAUGAUGUGGAAUAUAACAACAUGGAAUUAGAAGAGGGAGAACUCAUGGAAGAUGCAGCUGCUGCAGGACCCGCAGGUAGUAGCCAUGGUUAUGUGGGUUCCAGUAGUAGAAUAUCAAGAAGAACACAUUUAUGCUCCGCUGCUACCAGUAGUUUACUAGACAUUGAUCCAUUAAUUUUAAUACAUUUGUUGGACCUUAAGGACCGGAGCAGUAUAGAAAAUUUGUGGGGCUUACAGCCUCGCCCACCUGCUUCACUUCUGCAGCCCACAGCAUCAUAUUCUCGAAAAGAUAAAGACCAAAGGAAGCAACAGGCAAUGUGGCGAGUGCCCUCUGAUUUAAAGAUGCUAAAAAGACUCAAAACUCAAAUGGCCGAAGUUCGAUGUAUGAAAACUGAUGUAAAGAAUACACUUUCAGAAAUAAAAAGCAGCAGUGCUGCUUCUGGAGACAUGCAGACAAGCCUUUUUUCUGCUGACCAGGCAGCUCUGGCUGCAUGUGGAACUGAAAACUCUGGCAGAUUGCAGGAUUUGGGAAUGGAACUCCUGGCAAAGUCAUCAGUUGCCAAUUGUUACAUACGAAACUCCACAAAUAAGAAGAGUAAUUCGCCCAAGCCAGCUCGAUCCAGUGUAGCAGGUAGUCUAUCACUUCGAAGAGCAGUGGACCCUGGAGAAAAUAGUCGUUCAAAGGGAGACUGUCAGACUCUGUCUGAAGGCUCCCCAGGAAGCUCUCAGUCUGGGAGCAGGCACAGUUCUCCCCGAGCCUUGAUACAUGGCAGUAUCGGUGAUAUUCUGCCAAAAACUGAAGACCGGCAGUGUAAAGCUUUGGAUUCAGAUGCUGUUGUGGUUGCAGUUUUCAGUGGCUUGCCUGCGGUUGAGAAAAGGAGGAAAAUGGUCACCUUGGGGGCUAAUGCUAAAGGAGGUCAUCUGGAAGGACUGCAGAUGACUGAUUUGGAAAAUAAUUCUGAAACUGGAGAGUUACAGCCUGUACUACCUGAAGGAGCUUCAGCUGCCCCUGAAGAAGGAAUGAGUAGCGACAGUGACAUUGAAUGUGACACUGAGAAUGAGGAGCAGGAAGAGCAUACCAGUGUGGGCGGGUUUCACGACUCCUUCAUGGUCAUGACACAGCCCCCGGAUGAAGAUACACAUUCCAGUUUUCCUGAUGGUGAACAAAUAGGCCCUGAAGAUCUCAGCUUCAAUACAGAUGAAAAUAGUGGAAGGCAACUGCCCCUCUCCAUUUGGUGCCACUUGGUUACUCUGCAACCUCAGCUUUCCAAUGGAUUCGAAAAAAUGUCCUAAUUUAUAGUUCAUCUGGCUCGUUUGCAUUGUAAGAGUAGAAGAAAUGCUCCUUCUACCCCUACAUCCCGGAGUGGAAGCUGGAAGUGCUGUGAUUUAAAAAUGUAUAUAUGUAAAACACACAUUUUAUUGAAUGUAAAACAUGAGUGUAAUUAAUCCUAAAACCAGAAUUCAGAAAAUGAGCCAUUUUUAAUUUUUUUAUCUAGUUUUUUAAAUGUUUGAAUUAUAAAGGUGAUAAGAUUAGAAAAAUUUGGGAAAUAGAAAACCCCAAGAGCUAUUUUCUUUUUUGCAUAUUCAUUUGAAUUUUUAUGUGGUAAUAUUUUUAGAUUUCUCCUCAUUCUACCUCUCAUUCUCACAUCUACCAAUACAUGCCUUCAUAGUCUAGAUUUAUAGAAGUUUUAGAACUCUGCUUAGGGAUGCUUAAGAGCAAAUGGUAAGAUUAGCCACAGUGUAGUUUGGGACAUCAGUAGUACGGGCUGCUCUCUUUCUAAAAUCCUUUUCUCUGGCUGGCAUGUUGACCGGGAGUCUCCCUUCCAUUCCUGCUCUGCAGACCCUGCGGGCCAGAGUCCUUGCCCGAGACCUUCAGGUCAGUCAGUGUCUCCUGGUGUGCAUUUGGGAAAGGCUGCUGCAUAGGCUCACCUCCCACUGGGUUUCAUUUGACCUAGUGAACCCGUAGCAACUCGAUUUGGCUUAAUUGGCCACCCCUAAUCCUGUAGCUGUCAUACUACUCAAUGUAAUGACUAGCAGGGACAACUUUUUCAUCAUCUUUAGUUAAACUCCAGUUACUCAUUUGGAAAAUGGUUUCCCCAAAUGUGUAUCAUUCUUGACAGUUUUUCACAUUUGUUUCCCUGGUCCUAAAGCAAGAUUAUAAAAAUCAAAUAGAACCUGUGUGUGAGGGCCCUUGUUUGCACAAUGAGGAGAGGACACACUUCAUCUGGAGGUUGCGUGACUGGGGCAGCAUCCUACAGCUCAGCAUAAGAGGCAGGCUCAACCAACUGCCCAGGGAAGAGCGCUUCUUACUAAACAUAUUCAACAGUUGGGGCUCUCAGAAAAGAAUGUGACUUGUUUUAAAUGUAAGUAAGGGAUCUUCCAUAAGGUUAUUCCUAGGCCAAGCAAAAGGAGGUUCCCUAAAGCACAAUAGAAAAAGUGUUCUUUACUAAUUGCUGUUAAGAUGACAGAUGGGGCUGGGCGUGGUGUCUCACACCUGUAAAUCCCAGCACUUGGGGAGGCCAAGGCAGGCAGAUCACUUGAGGUCAGGUGUUCAAGACCAGUCUGGCCAACAUGGCAAAACCCCGUCUCUACUAAAAACACAAAAGCCAGGCGUGGUGGCCGACGCCUGUAAUCCCAGCAUCCUGGGAGGCUGAGGCACAAGAAUUGCUUGAACCUGGGAGGCAGAGGUUGCAGUGAGCCGAGAUUGCACCACUGCACUCCAGCCAGGGUGACACAGCAGGACUCUUGUCUCAAAAAAGAAAAAAAAAAAAAAAAAAGACAGAUGGAAACUUGCAAUCAAAAAGAAAAUGAUGCACUUAGGGAGGCCGAGGUGGGAGGGUGGAUCAUCUGAGGUCAGGAGUUCGAGACCAGCCUGGCCAACAUGGUGAAACCCCACCUCCACUAAUAAUAAUAAAAUGAGCUGGGUGUGGUGGCGGGCGCCUGUAAUCCCAGCUACUUGGGAGAUUGAGGCAGGAAAAUCGCUUGAACCUGGGAGGCAGAGGUUGUGGUGAGCCAAGAUCACGUCACUGCACUCCGGCCUGGGUGACAGAAUGAAACUCCAUCUCAAAAGAAGGAAAGGAAAUGAUGCACACUGACAGCAACAGGGGGCGGGUGUGGGGGGGAAUGCUCAGUUAUGCAGCUUGUCAGUACAGACAGUUGUUUCUGAUAAUUUGGUAACUUGGGUAAAUUUCUAUGAUGUUCAAAUGAUUUUACUGUACCUAGUGGUUCCCUUCUGUCUUGCUGUGUGCUGCUCCUUCAGAAAGAGGUGUUCCUUUUGAUCUAAGUAAUACUAUAUUUUAGGGAAUUUUUUCAAGUGUAACACUUACUAAUCAAAAUGUUCCUUUUCUGUCAUUCCCUGCUUCAGUAAACCCCUUCAAAUAUGUCCUUCUUUCAAAACUUCACCUUUUUUUUCUCAAUUGUUCAUUUGGUUCUAUAUAAAGUCAUGCCAAGGACUGAAUGAAUUUAGGGAAUUAGGAGUUGAAGAUUUUUGAAACUAUGUAAAAUUAAUUGUAAAGGCCUUCUUUACUGGUAGGCAGGAGAACAGUGCAGUGUAUUGACAAGGUUGACUCGUUUGGAAGGUCAGUUCCCUCCCUUCAGAUGCAGGUGUCGUAAGUGACUUCCCUCCCCCACAUUGUCCUUUUUGUCUCUGUCUCCUUUUACUCACUUAUCAGCAGUCCUUGGGAGGCUUUCCACCACAGCUCAUCUGAUGAUUUCCUUACUUUCUUCUAGCUUGAAACUCAAAGAGGCUAAGCGAAAGGGGAAAGCUUGGUUAGAUGCAGAGUUCUAAGAAUGAAGUAGUUGGGAGAUUUGAUGACCACCGCUUAGUCCUUGGCAGGUCGGGUUCCUCUUUUCUUUUAGGAUUAUAACACCACUCCCUCUCCUCGCAGUUCAGCUAAUGAAGAGAACAUGUAUAAGGCUAAAUACCUCUCUUCUGGGGUAAAAUAAUGUUACAGCAGCAUUUAGCAAAUCUUCUUUUUAAAUGUUCCAAGCUUCCAAACUUAACGUCCAUCUCAGGAUUUUAUUUUCCAGUUCUGAAGAAAUCUGCACAAAUUUAAACAGUAAAUAACUUACCUUUCCUUUAAAUAAAAAGACAAAUGACUAGUGGUUUUUAAAUUGCCAGGUUUUAUUAAGAUAAUUGGCAAAAUUUCAACAUACACCUUACCUGAAUGAACACUUUUAAUAAAAUAUGAAGGAUCACUCAUGACUACAACUGAACUCAAAAGUGAGAUGUAGAGCAGAUUUGUAAAUUGAUAAAUUUAUUUGGUAAGAAAUUAUUCACUUCAUUCGCUUCACUCCAUAGAGAAUUCUUUGCAGAGAAAUGUUAUGAACAAGAGAACAAAGCCUGUCUCUCACCAAAGAGCACCUAGAGUAAGAGUUUACAAUGAUGUAUCUGGAUUAUCUAAUUCAUCAAAGUUUAUUUCCUUUUCAAAAACAACUGCUGUGUCAGUCUGGAGUUCCCUAUUUCAUGUUUUCUAAUUAUUACAAUAAAUAGUCUUCAAAAUAGAAGAUAAAA